GUAGUACGGACUGGGCCUGGCCUGGGGCGUCCCCGCGAAGCCUGGGCCUGUCAGGCGGUUCCGUCCGGGUCUCGGCCACCGUCGAGUUCCGUCGAGUUCCGUCCCGGCCCUGCUCACAGCAGCGCCCUCGGAGCGCCCAGCACCUGCGGCCGGCCAGGCAGCGCGAUCCUGCGGCGUCUGGCCAUCCCGAAUGCUAUGGCCGCCGUCGCCGUCUUGCGGGCCUUCGGGGCAAGUGGGCCCAUGUGUCUCCGGCGCGGCCCCUGGGCCCAGCUCCCCGCCCGCUUCUGCAGCCGGGACCCGGCCGGGGCGGGGCGGCGGGAGUCGGAGCCGCGGCCCACCAGCGCGCGGCAGCUGGACGGCAUAAGGUCAGCCCCGGGCCGCGCGGGCUCCUCGCGUUGGUGCCGAGUCGGGGUCAGGGCGCCGCCAUUGACCCGGGGAGGACCCGGGGAACCGGAGCCCCGUUUACGCCCCUGGGGAGGGAACUCCCCGUGUCCCGGACCCGGGCCUGGCAGCGAGACGCGCAGGAACAUCGUCUUGAGCAAUCCCAAGAAGAGGAACGCGUUGUCACUUGCAAUGCUGAAGUCUCUCCAAAGUGACAUUCUUCAUGACGCUGACAGCAACGAUCUGAAAGUCAUUAUCAUCUCGGCUGAGGGGCCUGUGUUUUCUUCUGGGCAUGACUUAAAGGAGCUGACAGAGGAGCAAGGCCGUGAUUACCAUGCCGAAGUAUUUCAGACCUGUUCCAAGGUCAUGAUGCACAUCCGGAACCACCCCGUUCCCGUCAUUGCCAUGGUCAAUGGCCUGGCCGCGGCUGCCGGCUGUCAACUGGUUGCCAGCUGCGACAUUGCCGUGGCGAGCGACAAGUCCUCUUUUGCCACUCCUGGGGUGAACGUCGGGCUCUUCUGUUCUACCCCUGGGGUUGCCUUGGCAAGAGCAGUGCCUAGAAAGGUGGCCUUGGAGAUGCUCUUUACUGGUGAGCCCAUUUCUGCCCAGGAGGCCCUGCUCCACGGGCUGCUUAGCAAGGUGGUGCCAGAGGCGGAGCUGCAGGAGGAGACCAUGCGGAUCGCUAGGAAGAUCGCAUCGCUGAGCCGUCCGGUGGUGUCCCUGGGCAAAGCCACCUUCUACAAGCAGCUGCCCCAGGACCUGGGGACGGCUUACUACCUCACCUCCCAGGCCAUGGUGGACAACCUGGCCCUGCGGGACGGGCAGGAGGGCAUCACGGCCUUCCUCCAGAAGAGAAAACCUGUCUGGUCACACGAGCCAGUGUGAGUGGAGGCAGAGGAGUGAGGCCCACGGGCAGCGCCCAGGAGCCCACCUUCCCCUCUGGCCCAGCCACCACUGCCUCUCAGCUUCAACAGGUGACAGGCUGCUUUCGUGACUUGAUAUUGGUGUCAUAGCAUUUGGCCUACAUUAAAAGCCACAAUUUCAUGGGGAAAGGACAAAAUGGAGAGUGACUGAGGUGCUGACCUCAGUGCAAGGCUGGUGAACCCUGCAGCGGGCCAGCUAUGGUGGGAAGCCUGGCAUUUGGGGUGCUCCUUGCAACGUCUUAAGCAAGCGACCCCCCGACAUAGCAAAAGGUGGCAACCCAUGGAGGCAGAAAGAAGGACGCCAGCCUGACCCUUAUCUGAAACGUCCUAAGCAGAGUUAAUCCUGGCUGCUCAGGAGAGGCGACACAUUUCAAAUCUCCACGAGAUAUUCUCCACACAGAAAAUCUUCUUGAUUCUAUAGAGACUUAAUCAUGCCUAUGGCUUUGAAUAAUCUUAUGUGAUUUAAAUAAAUUAAAUCUUUAUAGAGA